ACGCCGAUUCCAUAUGGGCGCCGGCGCGGAGCGCCGCGGGGCAGCGCGGGGUCGCCAUGGCUGAGCUGCAGCAGCUCCGGGUGCAGGAGGCGGUGGAGUCCAUGGUGAAGAGUCUGGAAAGAGAGAACAUCCGGAAGAUGCAGGUGAGCGGCCCGAGGCCCAGCAGAGGCGCUGCCAACGUGAAAGACCAGAAAGGCGAGGACUUCCGGCCUCCCCGUUGGCCAGGUCAUGCCUGCUUCUCUUGCGCCCAACCUCGCUUCACACAGCGCGGGUUUCUACACUGUUCUUCUCUGAGCCCCGCAAUGCCUCUGUGUGUUUCGGUCCUGCUUCUCUCACGGAGUAUGCGUUUCCCAGAUAGUGCCCCUUGAGUCAUUGAUUAGUGGGUCGGCUGCCCUCUGGUGGAAUUUGUAUUGCUAGGUUGCUGACCUCUGAACCCCAUGGAAGAGGCUCCUGGUUUUCAGAAUUUGGCUUCGUCAGACCACCCUACCCUCACCCACUCGGGCGAACCUCUGUUCACCCAACCAUCGGUGCAACAGGUGCCGAUGAGCUAGCAGCAAGGACACCAUGAAACACUACACUAGACAUUGAGGAUAAUUUUCCCCAGUGGUGGUUUUAAGGUCCUGGUGUCUAUUCUCAGGGAAGGUGAAAGCAGAAGGUGGAGAGAGAGGUGCAAAUAUCCACGUGGCCUUCUAACUCCUGUAGUGCUCCAUAGUCAUCUCUGUCCCCAGAGACUUUCCUACCUAACCUCUCUGCCCUUUCUCCCCAGGGUCUCAUGUUCCGGUGCAGCGCCAGCUGUUGUGAGGACAGCCAGGCCUCCAUGAAGCAGGUGCACCAGUGCAUCGAGCGCUGCCAUGUGCCUCUGGCUCAAGCCCAGGCUUUGGUCACCAGUGAGCUGGAGAAGUUCCAGGACCGCCUGGCCCGGUGCACCAUGCAUUGCAACGACAAAGCCAAAGAUUCAAUAGAUGCUGGGAGUAAGGAGCUUCAGGUGAAGCAGCAGCUGGACAGUUGUGUGACCAAGUGUGUGGAUGACCACAUGCACCUCAUCCCAACUAUGACCAAGAAGAUGAAGGAGGCUCUCUUAUCAAUUGGAAAAUAAAAGUAUUUGCCAGUGGCCAUCAGGGCUGAGGGCAAGAAUAUAUUUUUUAUAAGGAAUUGGGAAUUUUAGUCUUUUAAGCAAAGUUUACGAAUGAAGAAAUGAAGGAUGGCCACAAGCGUAAGGCAUAUGUCACUUGCCUCUGGACACUGGUUAUUUUAUGUUUCAGUCCCUAAAAAAUGAAAUGGAAAAAAGUGGUGCUAAAUCGAGUCAGAGAUAUUACAGGAGAGUUUUAGAGCUUAUUAUUUCCUGUGGCCAGUGCUUGUCCUGGCAGUAAGGCUUUCCCCUGUAACAAGCCAGAGCCCUCCAAGGUACCAGACUCUUCUUACUACACAGGUACUAACAGGCUGGCAGGUUAGAGUUGGUGGAGUCUGAGGAGAGAUAUUUUCUCUUUGUUGCCAACAUCCUGUUUACCAAAAGUGUCACCCCACCAUCUUCCAUAAGCUGUGAAACAAAAUCAAUGAGGUCACUAACUUAGAAGGGAAAGAAAGUUUUCUGGGUCUUUGUUUUCUUGAUUUGGGGUAAUUUAUACAAGGGCAUACAAGUUGAUUUUAAGAUGUGGAACUGGGAGGUAGACUAGUUUGGAUAAGAACUUUGAAAUGUUCCUUGUGGAUCCCCAUUUCUGGUCAUCAAGAUGUGGAUGUACAUUUCUUAAAAUUAUUACAUGCUGCAUCUUUCAGCCUGGAGACUGUGCAGAAACAUGAGAGGUGAUGACACACUAAUUAUGGGAAGCAGAAUUACUGGCUGAUGGCCCCUGAGGCUGUGUGUAACAAAAUGACAGGACAAUCUUGCAGUAACACUUUCCCCUUGAAGAGAAGGGGGUUUUGAUUGUGAUAUAUACUAGUAUCUAGGAAUGAACAGUAAAAGAGGAGCAGUUGGCUACUUGAUUACAACAGAGUAAAUGAAGUACUGGAUUUGGGAAAACCUGGUUUUAUUAGAACAUAUGGAAUGAAAGCCUACACCUAGCAUUGCCUACUUAGCCCCCUGAAUUAACAGAGCCCAAUUGAGACAAACCCCUGGCAACAGGAAAUUCAAGGGAGAAAAAGUAAGCAACUUGGGCUAGGAUGAGCUGACUCCCUUAGAGCAAAGGAGAGACAGCCCCCAUUACCAAAUACCAUUUUUGCCUGGGGCUUGUGCAGCUGGCAGUGUUCCUGCCCCAGCAUGGCACCUUAUUGUUUUGAUAGCAACUUCGUUGAAUUUUCACCAACUUAUUACUUGAAAUUAUAAUAUAGCCUGUCCGUUUGCUGUUUCCAGGCUGUGAUAUAUUUUCCUAGUGGUUUGACUUUAAAAAUAAAUAAGGUUUAAUUUUCUCCCCA